GAGGACGUUGCGUGCUCGCUCGCGCCAGGCGAGUCUCCGCGUCUCCCUCGCGAACUCGGUGAAAGGAAUUGGCGCCGUUCGACACCAGGCGGAUCCGCUCUGCAGCACGAACCCAUCUCCAGCCGCAGCCGCAGCCGCCGCCCGGGCCGAGGAGCAGCCGCAGCAGCCGCCACCAGUGGCCGAGUGAGCGGAGCCGAGUUUGAGGCAGCGCCUAGCGGUGAAUCGGGGCCCUCACCAUGAGUUCCUCGCCUGUUAAUGUAAAAAAGCUGAAGGUGUCGGAGCUGAAAGAGGAGCUCAAGAAGCGACGCCUUUCUGACAAGGGUCUCAAGGCCGAGCUCAUGGAGCGACUCCAGGCUGCGCUGGACGACGAGGAGGCCGGGGGCCGCCCCGCCAUGGAGCCCGGGAACGGCAGCCUAGACCUGGGCGGGGAUUCCGCUGGGCGCUCGGGAGCAGGCCUCGAGCAGGAGGCCGCGGCCGGCGGCGAUGAAGAGGAGGAGGAAGAGGAAGAGGAGGAGGAAGGAAUCUCCGCUCUGGACGGCGACCAGAUGGAGCUAGGAGAGGAGAACGGGGCCGCGGGGGCGGCCGACUCGGGCCCGAUGGAGGAGGAGGAGGCCGCCUCGGAAGACGAGAACGGCGACGAUCAGGGUUUCCAGGAAGGGGAAGAUGAGCUCGGGGACGAAGAGGAAGGCGCGGGCGACGAGAACGGGCACGGGGAGCAGCAGCCUCAACCGCCGGCGACGCAGCAGCAACAGCCCCAACAGCAGCGCGGGGCCGCCAAGGAGGCCGCGGGGAAGAGCAGCGGCCCCACCUCGCUGUUCGCGGUGACGGUGGCGCCGCCCGGGGCGAGGCAGGGCCAGCAGCAGGCGGGAGGUAAGAAGAAGGCGGAAGGCGGCGGAGGCGGCGGUCGCCCCGGGGCUCCGGCGGCGGGGGACGGCAAAACAGAACAGAAAGGCGGAGAUAAAAAGAGGGGUGUUAAAAGACCACGAGAAGAUCAUGGCCGUGGAUAUUUUGAGUACAUUGAAGAGAACAAGUAUAGCAGAGCCAAAUCUCCUCAGCCACCUGUUGAAGAAGAAGAUGAACACUUCGAUGACACAGUGGUUUGUCUUGAUACUUAUAAUUGUGAUCUACAUUUUAAAAUAUCAAGAGAUCGUCUCAGUGCUUCUUCCCUUACAAUGGAGAGUUUUGCUUUUCUUUGGGCUGGAGGAAGAGCAUCCUAUGGUGUGUCAAAAGGCAAAGUGUGUUUUGAGAUGAAGGUUACAGAGAAGAUCCCAGUAAGGCAUUUAUAUACAAAAGAUAUUGACAUACAUGAAGUUCGUAUUGGCUGGUCACUAACUACAAGUGGAAUGUUACUUGGUGAAGAAGAAUUUUCUUAUGGGUAUUCUCUAAAAGGAAUAAAAACAUGCAACUGUGAGACUGAAGAUUAUGGAGAAAAGUUUGAUGAAAAUGAUGUGAUUACAUGUUUUGCUAACUUUGAAAGUGAUGAAGUAGAACUCUCGUAUGCUAAGAAUGGACAAGAUCUUGGCGUUGCCUUCAAAAUCAGUAAGGAAGUUCUUGCUGGACGGCCACUGUUCCCGCAUGUUCUCUGCCACAACUGUGCAGUUGAAUUUAAUUUUGGUCAGAAGGAAAAGCCAUAUUUUCCAAUACCUGAAGAGUAUACUUUCAUCCAGAACGUCCCCUUAGAGGAUCGAGUUAGAGGACCAAAGGGGCCUGAAGAGAAGAAAGAUUGUGAAGUUGUGAUGAUGAUUGGCUUGCCAGGAGCUGGAAAAACUACCUGGGUUACUAAACAUGCAGCAGAAAAUCCAGGGAAAUAUAACAUUCUUGGCACAAAUACUAUUAUGGAUAAGAUGAUGGUGGCAGGUUUUAAGAAGCAAAUGGCAGAUACUGGAAAACUGAACACACUGUUGCAGAGAGCCCCCCAGUGUCUUGGGAAAUUUAUUGAGAUUGCUGCCCGAAAGAAGCGAAAUUUUAUUCUGGAUCAGACAAAUGUGUCUGCUGCUGCCCAGAGGAGAAAAAUGUGCCUGUUUGCAGGCUUCCAGCGAAAAGCUGUUGUAGUUUGCCCAAAAGAUGAAGACUAUAAGCAAAGAACACAGAAGAAAGCAGAAGUAGAGGGGAAAGACCUACCAGAACAUGCGGUCCUCAAAAUGAAAGGAAACUUUACCCUCCCAGAGGUAGCUGAGUGCUUUGAUGAAAUAACCUAUGUUGAACUUCAGAAGGAAGAAGCCCAAAAACUCUUGGAGCAAUAUAAGGAAGAAAGCAAAAAGGCUCUUCCACCAGAAAAGAAACAGAACACUGGCUCAAAGAAAAGCAAUAAAAAUAAGAGUGGCAAGAACCAGUUUAACAGAGGUGGUGGCCAUAGAGGACGUGGAGGAUUCAAUAUGCGUGGUGGAAAUUUCAGAGGAGGAGCCCCUGGGAAUCGUGGCGGAUAUAAUAGGAGGGGCAACAUGCCACAGAGAGGUGGUGGCGGUGGAGGAAGUGGUGGAAUCGGCUAUCCAUACCCUCGUGCCCCUGUUUUUCCUGGCCGUGGUAGUUACUCAAACAGAGGGAACUACAACAGAGGUGGAAUGCCCAACAGAGGGAACUACAACCAGAACUUCAGAGGACGAGGAAACAAUCGUGGCUACAAAAAUCAAUCUCAGGGCUACAACCAGUGGCAGCAGGGUCAAUUCUGGGGUCAGAAGCCAUGGAGUCAGCAUUAUCACCAAGGAUAUUAUUGAAUACCCAAAUAAAACGAACUGAUACAUAUUUCUCCAAAACCUUCACAAGAAGUCGACUGUUUUCUUUAGUAGGCUAACUUUUUAAACAUUCCACAAGAGGAAGUGCCUGCGGGUUCCUUUUUUAGAAGCUUUGUGGGUUGAUUUUUUUUCUUUUCUUUUUUGUACAUUUUUAAUUGCAGUUUAAAAGUGAAUCGUAAGAGAACCUCAGCAUUGUGCACGAUAAGAGAAUGUGUCAGUAUUUCAGGGUUCUACAUUUUAUCUGUAAAAUGUGACUUUUUUUUUUUUUUAUCACAACAGAAGUAAAAUGUUGCUUUGUACCUGGUGUCUUUUAUUAAGAAUUUACUCCCCCCAUUUCUCACAGAGAAUAACAGUCGGGAGUCAUUGUCACAAUAUAAUAGAAAUGUUAGCAACCAGAUUCAUGUAAGGACUAAGUGGUCCUCAUGAAUUGCAUUAAGACUCUGUACUGCUCAUAUUACACUCCAUCCUCUCUGUAGUUUGCUGGGUAGUGGAGGGGGUAAGCUAAAUCAUAGUUUCUGACAAUAACUGGGAAGGUUUUUUCUUAAAAUAACAAUGGAAUUGGUAUAAUUGGGAUUGAAAACUAAAACUUGGAACUAAGAUAGAGAAGAUGGAGUGUAUGUAGAAGGGCUGUUAAAAAUGUAAAACUUGGUUGCAUUAUUUGUGGAGGCUCAAACUUGUGAAGGUUAAUACCAUAAUUUUUCCAUUUGUUCUGCAUUUUGAUUCUGAAAAGAAAGCUGGCUUUGCCCAUUUCUUAUUAAAAAAACUUGUUGUAAAUCCAGUUGUCUAAUGGGAUCUAUAUGAAGUUAGCCAUGUCUGUAUGCCCUUCUCCCACAAAAUACUGUAUAACUAGUGUGCUUGUAGUAGUUAACUCCACCAUCUUUGUAAGCUAAUGAAAUUGUGAGUCACCCAUUUAUAUCUUAAUUUUUAAUCAUGUCAGUUCUUGAAUGGGUAUCUCCUUAGCCUGCUGAUUUCUUUUUCUUUCUAAAGAAAGUGGGUGGAGAAAUUAAUUUAGACGUUUGUUUGCAAUAAAAAGAAUUCAUUUUACUCUUGUUUUGGGAUUCUCGCCAUCAAGGUUCAAAAUCCCUUUAUAUAACUCCCAAGAGGAGAAAUUUAUUAAGUGUGUGCUUUCUGGACAGCUUAUUCUUUACUCUGCAUAGAACAUUUAGGUUUUAAAAACUUAAAUGUAUACUGACAAUUGAUACAUAAUUAUGAAGUAAAGUUGAAUUCUUCCCUUCCCCUCCCCCCCAGACAACUUUUAACAUAUUUAAUGAGGGGAAAAGGUACUGGCUGGGAGAAGUUAACACUGAGUUUAUCAUCUUUACAGAAUGCUAAUGCUGUCCUCAACUGAUUAUUUUAUAUACAUAUAUAUGAUACAUGAAACUCUGGGAUCAGAUGCUUUUAGAAGCCAUCAUGCAAGCCAGUCAUUGAUGUCACUGCUACACAACACUGCUAACUUGACUGUAGCUAUGUAAUAACAUUAGAUCCCCUAAUUGUAAUUAUAUUGGGUUUGCACAGAACACUUUAAUCUUCCCCUCACCAAUGUGAAGUGAGGAAUCAGGAGUCAAACUGUAGAACUAAAAUUUGACUUCAGUCUAGCGUUUCCUUGGUGUUUUUAGGUUGCUUUGGUAAGUUUAGGUUUGCUAUAUUUCUGAUUGCUUAGAAUUUUGUUUUAGCCCUUUAAAAUCAGAUCAUAAAUAUGAAUUCAUACUUCUAAGGAAUUUUCUUGCUAUAAGCUGGAGUUUAGGUGAUGUAUAGGUUCAGUUGAGACAUUUUUGGAACAGGCAAAUCCUUAGUUAACAUAAGAUAUUUAACAGUUGAAGAUAGUGUCAUGGAUUUUUAUCUUUUUUAGCAAGUAAUGCUAAGAACCACUGGCCUGAGCUACUACUCUUCAGUAUACAUUAUUAGGAUUGCAUAGACUUACUAGAGGAACAGUUUCAGGUUUUGAUGCUAAUCAGUGUUGUGUCCUAAAGUUGUCCUUUGUGCCUUUAAAAAGUUUUGGAUAUAUCUUCUAGUUUAAAAUUGCUUAUUAAGGAAUUCAUUUUAUAAUUGCAGUGGGAAAGUAAUGGUCAAGUAACACUAGGUAGACUAUCAUGCCUGUUUAGCCCAGAGAAUUUGGGGGGAGAGAGAAUAGAUAAAAAUGGCACCCAGAAAAAUGUUAAAAUCUUUAGUCAAGACUAGAAUUAAUACAAUUGUCUACACUUGUAUGGCAGAAAUAACCUUAUAAAGUGUUUAAGGAAUUCAGAGAAGGGAAUGUACCAAAUAAGCAACAGGGAGAAAAUUAGGUAAGAAGUAAGAUACGAACGAGAAACCUGAUUUAUUGCUCAUCCUUCCCUUGCCUCCCUAAUGGCAAGCAAAACUCUGAACAUCUGAAAAGGAUGUAGUUCUGGACAAAUCCUGACUACCCAGAGGAAACUCACUGUGAGAUUGCUGUUGAUUUGAAGGGUGCUUUCACUAAGGUUAUAUUUUAAAGUAGAAUAACACAUGCUGAGUGUAAACUGGCUUUGGAUUGGUCAGCUGCAGUAGUACAAAAACAGCAUAGAAUUUGAGAAAACUAAAACUGCUAUGAGAUAGCUAUGAGAAAACUAAAACUGCUAUGAGAUAGAAAUGAUGUAAAAUUAUGUGGAAAGUUUUCCCUCAUAUACUCACAUACAGCCUUUGAAGGGCUCUGGCUCUGACCGGUUGAUGGCCUUGAGCGAGAUGAAAUCAUGAAAUUGAGUCAAAUCAAUUUGACAUUGAAAUGACAAGAGGAAACUCUUAAAUACAUAAAAACAAGCUCUCAUUUGCCUAGGAUAGAUACUGUCUUAAAAAUAAAGACUGAACCUAGAUGUUCUGAGCACUAGCAACAAGGUAUUUUAACAAGUUUAAAGGAAUUCUCUGAAAAAGUUAUAAAAUUAUUCUAGGAAACAUAACCAUAAUAGUGUUUUAAGGGACUUUCACCUGGGGAUUUUAUAUUCAUGAACAGAGUGUAUUCUGUAUUUAAAAUGUCUCAUUUGUGGGAAUUGGAUGACAUGUUUUUUGAUAAAUUUAUUCACAAUAUAAAUUGACUUUUUAUUCUAGGACCAUGUGAAUAAUGGGUUCCAUUGCACAAAUACAAAUAUUUUAAUAGCUUCUUAGGCAGUGGUGUAGACAUCUUGGAUAUAAAUAAUUGUAGAUCUUGUAUAUUUGAUUUUUAAAAAACUAGAAUAAACAGAGAGGCAUAAACAUAUCUUAGAGUCCAAGUGGUAGUGUUUAGCAUUGGAUAUAAUAAAUGGAUGUUUUACAAAGUGUUUCCAUAAUUCUCUUCCUAUACAUAAAUGUCUUGUUUUCAAAAGUGGAUGGAACUUGGCUGGGUGUGGUGGCUCACGCCUGUAAUCCUAGCACUUUGGGAGGCCAAGGCGGGAGGAUCACUUGAGCUCAGGAGUUUGAGACCAUCCUGGGCAACAUAGUGAGACCUGGUCUCUUGAAAAAAAAAAAGUGGAUGGAACUUGUAGCAGAGAAUUUUAUCUACUUCUCAACCUGCUUCAGAAUACCCAUUUGAGAUGUUCCCCUGGAAAGAUGAACACAAUACUGCAUCUGAAGCCAUUUCUUCCCACCUAACAUUCUUAAAAUGAUUAGAGUCUAAACUUUGUCAUUCAUUCCUAAUUCUGGAGCUCUGAGGUUGAGGUGUUCAGAGUUUGGUGAAUAAUUGGGUUUAAGUUUUAACAUUUUAGUAAUAAUAAAAGCAAACACAUACAUGUUAAGGCCUGACAAUAGGUUGCAAUACCCAUGCAUUGGGACUCAUACCCAGCAUAAAUGGUGAGGGACUGAACAUUAGUGCUUUGAGCAAGAAUUGGUUAACUACCUGAGAUCUCUAAAACAGUAAUUUGAAUUACUAAUACAUAAACCACAAGUCUCUUCGAAUUGUUAAUUGCCUAAAUUUACCCUAAAACUUAGUUAACGCUGCAGUGCCUUUAUUAAAGCUUUUUUUUGGGGGGGGGUGUGGGCACAGCUACUCCAUAACUUUAAAUUUUAAAGCAUGAAGGUGAUCUAGCUAGUGUUAGUGCUUGAGUUGGUAGUUACAUAGGCUGCUCUUGAAUCGUCCUGUUUUCUUUGCCUAGUAUUAGCACCACAGGUACAUAUUUGUAAAAUAAGCAUUAAAAGUACUUUGUCCAGCUAA